GGAAGUAGCCGCAGGCAUGGCGGCGGCUAUGCCGCUUGCUCUGCUCGUCCUGUUGCUCCUGGGGCCCGGCGGCUGGUGCCUUGCAGAACCCCCACGCGACAGCCUGCGGGAGGAACUUGUCAUCACCCCGCUGCCUUCCGGGGACGUAGCCGCCACAUUCCAGUUCCGCACGCGCUGGGAUUCGGAGCUUCAGCGGGAAGGAGUGUCCCAUUACAGGCUCUUUCCCAAAGCCCUGGGGCAGCUGAUCUCCAAGUAUUCUCUACGGGAGCUGCACCUGUCAUUCACACAAGGCUUUUGGAGGACCCGAUACUGGGGGCCACCCUUCCUGCAGGCCCCAUCAGGUGCAGAGCUGUGGGUCUGGUUCCAAGACACUGUCACUGAUGUGGAUAAAUCUUGGAAGGAGCUCAGUAAUGUCCUCUCAGGGAUCUUCUGCGCCUCUCUCAACUUCAUCGACUCCACCAACACAGUCACUCCCACUGCCUCCUUCAAACCCCUGGGUCUGGCCAAUGACACUGACCACUACUUUCUGCGCUAUGCUGUGCUGCCGCGGGAGGUGGUCUGCACCGAAAACCUCACCCCCUGGAAGAAGCUCUUGCCCUGUAGUUCCAAGGCAGGCCUCUCUGUGCUGCUGAAGGCAGAUCGCUUGUUCCACACCAGCUACCACUCCCAGGCAGUGCAUAUCCGCCCUGUUUGCAGAAAUGCACGCUGUACUAGCAUCUCCUGGGAGCUGAGGCAGACCCUGUCAGUUGUAUUUGAUGCCUUCAUCACGGGGCAGGGAAAGAAAGACUGGUCCCUCUUCCGGAUGUUCUCCCGAACCCUCACGGAGCCCUGCCCCCUGGCUUCAGAGAGCCGAGUCUAUGUGGACAUCACCACCUACAACCAGGACAACGAGACAUUAGAGGUGCACCCACCCCCGACCACUACAUAUCAGGACGUCAUCCUAGGCACUCGGAAGACCUAUGCCAUCUAUGACUUGCUUGACACCGCCAUGAUCAACAACUCUCGAAACCUCAACAUCCAGCUCAAGUGGAAGAGACCCCCAGAGAAUGAGGCCCCCCCAGUGCCCUUCCUGCAUGCCCAGCGGUACGUGAGUGGCUAUGGGCUGCAGAAGGGGGAGCUGAGCACACUGCUGUACAACACCCACCCAUACCGGGCCUUCCCGGUGCUGCUGCUGGACACCGUACCCUGGUAUCUGCGGCUGUAUGUGCACACCCUCACCAUCACCUCCAAGGGCAAGGAGAACAAACCAAGUUACAUCCACUACCAGCCUGCCCAGGACCGGCUGCAACCCCACCUCCUGGAGAUGCUGAUUCAGCUGCCGGCCAACUCAGUCACCAAGGUUUCCAUCCAGUUUGAGCGGGCGCUGCUGAAGUGGACCGAGUACACGCCAGAUCCUAACCAUGGCUUCUAUGUCAGCCCAUCUGUCCUCAGCGCCCUUGUGCCCAGCAUGGUAGCAGCCAAGCCAGUGGACUGGGAAGAGAGUCCCCUCUUCAACAGCCUGUUCCCAGUCUCUGAUGGCUCUAACUACUUUGUGCGGCUCUACACGGAGCCGCUGCUGGUGAACCUGCCGACACCGGACUUCAGCAUGCCCUACAACGUGAUCUGCCUCACGUGCACUGUGGUGGCCGUGUGCUAUGGCUCCUUCUACAAUCUCCUCACCCGAACCUUCCACAUCGAGGAGCCCCGCACAGGUGGCCUGGCCAAGCGGCUGGCCAACCUUAUCCGGCGCGCCCGAGGUGUCCCCCCACUCUGAUUCUUGCCCUUUCCAGCAGCUGCAGCUGCCGUUUCUCUCUGGGGAGGGGAGCCCAAGGGCUGUUUCUGCCACUUGCUCUCCUCAGAGUUGGCUUUUGAACCAAAGUGCCCUGGACCAGGUCAGGGCCUACAGCUGUGUUGUCCAGUACAGGAGCCACGAGCCAAAUGUGGCAUUUGAAUUUGAAUUAACUUAGAAAUUCAUUUCCUCACCUGUAGUGGCCACCUCUAUAUUGAGGUGCUCAAUAAGCAAAAGUGGUCGGUGGCUGCUGUAUUGGACAGCACAGAAAAAGAUUUCCAUCACCACAGAAAGGUCGGCUGGCAGCACUGGCCAAGGUGAUGGGGUGUGCUACACAGUGUAUGUCACUGUGUAGUGGAUGGAGUUUACUGUUUGUGGAAUAAAAACGGCUGUUUCCGUG